AGCUUCCAUCGCUGGGCGGUCAACAAGUGCGGGCCUGGCUCAGCGCGGGGGGGCGCGGAGACCGCGAGGCGACCGGGAGCGGCUGGGUUCCCGGCUGCGCGCCCUUCGGCCAGGCCGGGAGCCGCGCCAGUCGGAGCCCCCGGCCCAGCGUGGUCCGCCUCCCUCUGGGCGUCCACCUGCCCGGAGUACUGCCAGCGGGCAUGACCGACCCACCAGGGGCGCCGCCGCCGGCGCUCGCAGGCCGCGGAUGAAGAAGAAAACCCGGCGCCGCUCGACCCGGAGCGAGGAGUUGACCCGGAGCGAGGAGUUGACCCUGAGUGAGGAAGCGACCUGGAGUGAAGAGGCGACCCAGAGUGAGGAGGCGACCCAGGGCGAAGAGAUGAAUCGGAGCCAGGAGGUGACCCGGGACGAGGAGUCGACCCGGAGCGAGGAGGUGACCAGGGAGGAAAUGGCGGCAGCUGGGCUCACCGUGACUGUCACCCACAGCAAUGAGAAGCACGACCUUCAUGUUACCUCCCAGCAGGGCAGCAGUGAACCAGUUGUCCAAGACCUGGCCCAGGUUGUUGAAGAGGUCAUAGGGGUUCCACAGUCUUUUCAGAAACUCAUAUUUAAGGGAAAAUCUCUGAAGGAAAUGGAAACACCGUUGUCAGCACUUGGAAUACAAGAUGGUUGCCGGGUCAUGUUAAUUGGGAAAAAGAACAGUCCACAGGAAGAGGUUGAACUAAAGAAGUUGAAACAUUUGGAGAAGUCUGUGGAGAAGAUAGCUGACCAGCUGGAAGAGUUGAAUAAAGAGCUUACUGGAAUCCAGCAGGGUUUUCUGCCCAAGGAUUUGCAAGCUGAAGCUCUCUGCAAACUUGAUAGGAGAGUAAAAGCCACAAUAGAGCAGUUUAUGAAGAUCUUGGAGGAGAUUGACACACUGAUCCUGCCAGAAAAUUUCAAAGACAGUAGAUUGAAAAGGAAAGGCUUGGUAAAAAAGGUUCAGGCAUUCCUAGCCGAGUGUGACACAGUGGAGCAGAACAUCUGCCAGGAGACUGAGCGGCUGCAGUCUACAAACUUUGCCCUGGCCGAGUGAGGUGUAGCAGAAAAAGGCUGUGCUGCCCUGAAGAAUGGCGCCACCAGCUCUGCCGUCUCUGGAGCGGAAUUUACCUGAUUUCUUCAGGGCUGCUGGGGGCAACUGGCCAUUUGCCAAUUUUCCUACUCUCACACUGGUUCUCAAUGAAAAAUAGUGUCUUUGUGAUUUUGAGUAAAGCUCCUAUCUGUUUUCUCCUUCUGUCUCUGUGGUUGUACUGUCCAGCAAUCCACCUUUUCUGGAGAGGGCCACCUCUGCCCAAAUUUUCCCAGCUGUUUGGACCUCUGGGUGCUUUCUUUGGGCUGGUGAGAGCUCUAAUUUGCCUUGGGCCAGUUUCAGGUUUAUAGGCCCCCUCAGUCUUCAGAUACAUGAGGGCUUCUUUGCUCUUGUGAUCGUGUAGUCCCAUAGCUGUAAAACCAGAAUCACCAGGAGGUUGCACCUAGUCAGGAAUAUUGGGAAUGGCCUAGAACAAGGUGUUUGGCACAUAAGUAGACCACUUAUCCCUCAUUGUGACCUAAUUCCAGAGCAUCUGGCUGGGUUGUUGGGUUCUAGACUUUGUCCUCACCUCCCAGUGACCCUGACUAGCCACAGGCCAUGAGAUACCAGGGGGCCGUUCCUUGGAUGGAGCCUGUGGUUGAUGCAAGGCUUCCUUGUCCCCAAGCAAGUCUUCAGAAGGUUAGAACCCAGUGUUGACUGAGUCUGUGCUUGAAACCAGGCCAGAGCCAUGGAUUAGGAAGGGCAAAGAGAAGGCACCAGAAUGAGUAAAGCAGGCAGGUGGUGAAGCCAACCAUAAACUUCUCAGGAGUGACAUGUGCUUCCUUCAAAGGCAUUUUUGUUAACCAUAUCCUUCUGAGUUCUAUGUUUCCUUCACAGCUGUUCUAUCCAUUUUGUGGACUGUCCCCCACCCCCACCCCAUCAUUGUUUUUAAAAAAUUAAGGCCUGGCGCAGCAGCUCAUGCCUAUAAUCCCAGCACUUUGGGAGGCUGAGGCGGGCGGAUCACUUGAGGCCAGGAGUUUGAGACCAGCCCAGGCAACAUAGCAAAACCCCAUUCUGCUUUAAAAAAAAAAAAAAAAAAAAUUAGCUUGGCGUAGUGGCAUGUGCCUAUAAUCCCAGCUACUGGGGAGGCUGAGGCACAAGAAUCAUUUGAACCUGGGAGGUAGAGGUUGCUGUGAGCCGAGAUUACGCCCCUGCACUCCAGCCUGGGUCACAGAGUGAGACUCCAUCUCAGAAAAAAAAAAAAUUGAGUCAGGUGCAGUAGCUCCUUCCUGUAGUCCCAGCUACUUGGGAGGCUGAGGCUAGAGGAUCACUUGAGCCCAGGAGUUUGAGUCUAGUCUGGGCAACAUAGCAAGACCCCAUCUCUAAAAUUUAAGUAAGUAAAAGUAGAUAAAUAAAAAGAAAAAAAAACUGUUUAUGUGCUCAUCAUAAAGUAGAAGAGUGGUUUGCUUUUUUUUUUUUUUUUGGAUUAAUGAGGAAAUCAUUCUGUGGCUCUAGUCAUAAUUUAUGCUUAAUAACAUUGAUAGUAGCCCUUUGCGCUAUAACUCUACCUAAAGACUCACAUCAUUUGGCAGAGAGAGAGUCGUUGAAGUCCCAGGAAUUCAGGACUGGGCAGGUUAAGACCUCAGACAAGGUAGUAGAGGUAGACUUGUGGACAAGGCUCGGGUCCCAGCCCACCGCACCCCAACUUUAAUCAGAGUGGUUCACUAUUGAUCUAUUUUUGUGUGAUAGCUGUGUGGCGUGGGCCACAACAUUUAAUGAGAAGUUACUGUGCACCAAACUGCCGAACACCAUUCUAAACUAUUCAUAUAUAUUAGUCAUUUAAUUCUUACAUAACUUGAGAGGUAGACAGAUAUCCUUAUUUUAGAGAUGAGGAAACCAAGAGAACUUAGGUCAUUAGCGCAAGGUUGUAGAGUAAGCGGCAAAGCCAAGACACAAAGCUGGGUGGUUUGGUUUCAGAGCCAGUGCUUUUCCCCUCUACUGUACUGCCUCUCAACCAACACAGGGUUGCACAGGCCCAUUCUCUGAUUUUUUUCCUCUUGUCCUCUGCCUCUCCCUCUAGCUCCCACUUCCUCUCUGCUCUAGUUCAUUUUCUUUAGAGCAGCCCGAGUGAUCAUGAAGUGCAAAUCUUGCCAUGUCAGUCCCCUGCUUAGAACCCUCCAAUGGCUCACUUUCUCUUUAGGCAAAAGUCUUUACCCCAUGCCUUCUCCCAUCUCAUCUCAACCCCCUCAUUUGUUGGCUGUCUGCUGUCAGCCACUCUUCUUUCAGGUCCUCAGAUGCACUGCACCCUCUCCUGCCUGGGGGUCUUUGCUCCUGCUACUACCUCUGCUUGAACAGCUCCUCACCUUCCUUCCUCCAACCCUACCCUUGUAUAGGUGACUUUUGUUCAUCCUUCAGAAUUCAACUCACAUGUCUCUUGCAUGGAGAACCCUCACCUACUGUGUUGAGACCCUGUCCAGCCCCCAGGUGGGAUCCUCUCUCGACUUCCCAUACAUUUCUUUCACAGCAUUUACAUAGUCCAUGAUAGUUUACUUGUGGGAUUAUUUGGUUAAUCUUUGCCUUUAACACCAGGGUUCCUUGGGUGAAGGAGCUUCUUUAUCUUGGUAACAGCAUUAUUUCAAGCAUAACUUGUAAUAUAGUUAUAUUACAUAUAUAACAUAUAUAUAUAUAACAUAACAUAUAUAACAUAUAUAACAAGCAUAACUUGUUAUAUAGUCUUGUAUAUAGUAAGACCUCAAUAAAUAUUUGGAGAACAAA